AUCCCCGAACCCCGCUUUCCGGCCCGCGGCGACCCCAGGCAACUGUUGUGGCUGCCGCAUUGCUCCCGCCGGGCUGUAGCUGAGCGCGGAGCCCGUGGGGACCGGUGAGAUGGAACUGUUUUCCCGCGUUGAGACGUGCGGUCCGCUUGUGCUUUUAGAACUAAAGACUGCUGCAGAGUCCGGAGGAAGAAGUCACCUAGAAAAAUCUGGGACAGGGCAGUAAGCUUCCUUCUUAAUGUUUGACCUUUGGGGGCCGAUGUGUGAUACCUCGGAUUUGAAUCAAGAAUCUCCAAGCCCAUUUUCCGCAUGCAUGUAAACGUGAUGUACCGGGAUGGGGUCUGGUGGUGGAGGAGGAGCCAGCCUGACGGAUAAGCUUUUCCAGUGGCAGGGACUUGUGUUAAUUUCUUUUUUCUUUUUUUUUCUUUUUUCCGAGACAGAGUUUCACUCUGUCGCCCAGGCGGGAGUGCAGUGGCGCGAUCUCGGCUCACUGCAACCUCUGCCUCCUGGGUUCAAGCAAUUCUCCUGCCUCAGCCUCCCAAGUAGCUGGGAAUACAGGUGUGCGCCACCACGCCCGGCUAAUUUUUGUGUUUUUAGUAGAGACGGGGUUUCACUAUGUUGGCCAGGCUGGUCUCGAACUCCUGACCUCGUGAUUCUCCCGCCUCAGCCUCCCAAAGUGCUGGGAUUACAGGCGUGAGCCACUGCGCUCGGCCAACUUGUGUUAAUUUCUUAAACUUGCGUGAUCACCUGGUGUACUUGUUGAAAAAUACAGCUCCCUGGAGUGGCAGGAUCAGAAUCUGCCGAGGUGGACCGUGGGAAUCUGUCAUUUUUAAACAAGUGUCCCAGGUGGUUCUUUUGCUGAGGCAAGUGUGGGAAAUGUUGUGUGAACCCACGCUCAUCCAGUCUUCCUUGUGACCGGCAGUCCACUGUGCGCAACGCUGCAGCCAUACAGAGGGACAACUCGAAGUUAGAACUAGCACCUUGGUCUUGUUGGAAUAAGCAGAUCUGAGUAGAGCCAGCUGCAGUCUUAUGGUUGUUUAGCAGAAGUUAUUCUUCUUAGCAGAGAAUAUUAUACGGUCAUUUUCCAGAACUGUAAAAACUCUAUCAUUUGUUUUAAACCAGAUGAUGUGCUUCAUUUCUGUCUUUGACGUCUUCAGUUUCUUCUCCCCUGGCUUUACCUCCUUUGUUAUCAGUUUGUGCUUUGGUUUUGCUGCCAACCUUAUAGGUUUAGGUUUGGCGGCAAAGGCACUAGACUCUGGUGCCUUCUUUUCCUUCGUUGUCUUAAGCCCUUCUUUUCCUCUGCCCUCAUGCCCUCACCACUUCACUCUUUUGAAGGUCAUAAUGAACACAAGGUCAGAGAUCCCUUUUUUGGCGCCAAGCACCCUGGGCUUUUUUGAGAUGGAGUCUCACUGUGUCACCCAGGCAGUGGCGCGAAUCUGCCCACUGCAGCCUCCAUCUCCCUGGUUGAAGCAAUUUUCCUGUCUCAGCCUCCUGAGUAGCUGGGACUACAGGUGCAAGCCACGACACCUGGCUAAUUUUUCUGUUUUUAGUAGAGACGGGGUUUCACCAUGCUGAUCAGGCUGGUCUCAAACUCCUGACCUCAAAUAAUCCACCCACCUUGGCCUCCCAAAGUGCUAGGAUUACAGGUGUGAGCCCCUGCGCCUGGCCUUUCUUUGUUUUGUUUUGUUUAAGACAGAGUCUCACUGUGUCACCCAGGCAGGAGUGCAGUAGCAUAAUCUCGGCUCACUGCAACCUCUGUCUCCCAGGCUCAAGCGAUCCUCCUACCUCAGGAGUUCAGGACCAGCCUGGGCAACAUAGUGAGCCCCUCUCUACAAAAAAAAAAAAAAAAUUAAAAAAAUUAAUAAAACACAAGAUUGGCCUGUGUGGUGAGAGAGUAUUGAAUCCAACAAACGGGAACUGGUUAGUGAGGCCCAAGAUGCAAUGGUGGCCGCACCAUGAGUACCUGGGACCACAGGUGCGUGCCACCACACCCAGCUAAUUUUUUGUAUCUUUGGUAGAGACGGGGUUUCACCAUGUUUGCCAGGCUGGUCUCCAACUUCCGACCUCAAAUGAUCUACCCGCCUCGGCCUCCCAAAGUGCUGAGAUAACAGGCGUGAGACAUGGCGCCCGGCCUAAAGUUUUUUUUUUAAUUCCACCUUAAAACUCAUCUGUUACUGUGUUUGUUCUGCCACCUUUGCAAUUCCCUUUCUCUGUUAGGGGAAUGUGCUUAAUGGUUCAGUCCUCACAGCUGUCCUUUCCUUACCAUCUGCUUUUAUUUGAAAGGUAGCGUGGAGUCAUGAUUAAAUAGCCGGCCACUAAUGCCAAAUUGGCAGGGUUCUGCUACUCAACAGUUUGGUAGGACCUUGGUUUGAGUUCCUGAGAUCUAGUUGGUGAGAGACAUGAUGUUCUACCGGUUGCUGUCGAUUGUUGGAAGACAAAGAGCCAGCCCAGGAUGGCAGAACUGGUCCUCUGCAAGAAACAGCACGUCAGCUGCCGAGGCGCGUUCCAUGGCCCUGCCCACCCAGGCACAGGUGGUCAUCUGUGGAGGUGGAAUCACGGGCACUUCUGUGGCCUAUCACCUCUCCAAAAUGGGGUGGAAGGAUAUUGUCCUUUUGGAGCAGGGCAGGCUGGCUGCUGGCUCUACCAGGUUCUGUGCUGGCAUCCUGAGCACUGCCAGGCACUUGACCAUUGAGCAGAAGAUGGCAGACUACUCAAACAAACUCUACUAUCAGUUAGAGCAAGAAACAGGGAUCCAAACAGGUUACACAAGGACAGGCUCAAUCUUUCUGGCCCAAACUCAGGACCGACUGAUCUCCCUGAAGCGCAUCAACGCAGGGCUGAAUGUUAUAGGUAUCCCUUCUGAGAUCAUCUCCCCCAAGAAAGUGGCCGAGCUUCACCAUCUCCUCAACGUGCACGACCUGGUGGGGGCCAUGCAUGUUCCCGAGGAUGCAGUGGUGUCUUCCGCUGACGUGGCUCUUGCCCUGGCAAGUGCUGCCUCCCAAAAUGGUGUUCAGAUCUAUGACCGGACAUCUGUUCUUCAUGUAAUGGUCAAAAAAGGUCAAGUUACUGGAGUGGAGACCGAUAAAGGACAGAUUGAAUGCCAGUAUUUUGUCAACUGUGCUGGCCAGUGGGCAUACGAGCUGGGUCUGUCCAACGAGGAGCCGGUUAGUAUCCCGCUACAUGCCUGCGAACACUUCUACCUCCUGACUCGCCCCUUGGAGACCCCUCUGCAGAGCAGCACACCAACUAUUGUGGAUGCUGAUGGAAGAAUUUAUAUUCGGAACUGGCAGGGUGGCAUCCUGUCUGGGGGCUUUGAGAAGAACCCGAAACCAAUUUUCACUGAGGGCAAGAACCAGCUGGAGAUUCAGAAUCUACAGGAAGACUGGGAUCACUUUGAGCCUCUGUUGAGUUCCCUUCUGAGGAGGAUGCCAGAAUUAGAGACUCUGGAGAUCAUGAAGUUGGUGAACUGCCCAGAGACCUUCACACCAGACAUGAGGUGCAUCAUGGGCGAGUCUCCUGCAGUGCAGGGCUACUUUGUCCUGGCAGGAAUGAACUCUGCUGGCCUUUCAUUUGGUGGAGGAGCCGGAAAGUACCUUGCCGAAUGGAUGGUACAUGGUUAUCCCUCAGAAAACGUUUGGGAAUUGGACCUGAAACGUUUUGGAGCCCUCCAGAGCAGCCGCACCUUUCUGCGCCACCGGGUCAUGGAAGUCAUGCCUUUGAUGUAUGAUCUGAAGGUUCCCCGCUGGGACUUCCAGACCGGUAGGCAGUUACGCACCUCUCCUCUCUACGACCGGCUGGAUGCACAGGGAGCCAGGUGGAUGGAGAAACAUGGAUUUGAGAGGCCAAAGUACUUUGUUCCCCCCGACAAGGACCUCCUGGCAUUGGAGCAGAGCAAGACUUUCUAUAAGCCAGAUUGGUUUGACAUCGUGGAGUCUGAAGUCAAGUGCUGUAAGGAAGCUGUGUGUGUCAUUGACAUGUCCUCUUUCACAAAGUUUGAGAUAACAUCCACUGGGGAUCAGGCAUUAGAAGUUCUACAGUACCUCUUCUCCAAUGACCUGGAUGUGCCUGUGGGCCACAUUGUGCAUACUGGCAUGCUCAACGAGGGUGGAGGGUAUGAAAAUGACUGCAGCAUAGCACGACUGAACAAGCGCAGUUUCUUCAUGAUCUCUCCAACCGACCAGCAGGUCCACUGUUGGGCCUGGCUUAAGAAACACAUGCCGAAAGACAGCAACCUGCUCCUGGAGGACGUCACCUGGAAGUACACAGCCCUCAAUCUGAUUGGCCCUCGAGCUGUGGAUGUGCUGUCUGAGUUGUCCUAUGCCCCUAUGACUCCAGACCACUUCCCAAGCCUCUUUUGCAAGGAGAUGAGUGUGGGCUAUGCAAAUGGGAUCCGGGUGAUGAGCAUGACGCACACAGGAGAGCCAGGAUUCAUGCUCUACAUCCCCAUAGAGUACGCCCUGCAUGUAUACAAUGAAGUGAUGAGUGUUGGCCAGAAAUACGGAAUCCGGAAUGCUGGGUAUUACGCUCUUCGCAGUCUCCGAAUUGAGAAGUUUUUUGCCUUCUGGGGUCAGGAUAUAAAUAACCUCACCACGCCCCUGGAAUGUGGACGAGAGUCUCGGGUGAAAUUAGAGAAGGGCAUGGAUUUCAUUGGUCGCGACGCCCUCCUGCAGCAGAAGCAGAAUGGAGUGUAUAAACGCCUCACCAUGUUCAUCCUGGACGACCAUGAUUCAGACCUAGACCUUUGGCCUUGGUGGGGAGAGCCCAUUUACCGGAAUGGGCAGUAUGUUGGCAAGACCACCAGCAGUGCCUACAGCUACAGCCUGGAGCGCCACGUUUGCCUGGGCUUUGUGCACAAUUUUUCUGAGGACACGGGGGAAGAGCAAGUGGUGACAGCAGAUUUCAUCAACCGGGGAGAGUAUGAGAUUGACAUCGCGGGAUACCGCUUCCAGGCCAAGGCCAAGCUCUACCCUGUCGCCUCCCUCUUCACCCAGAAGCGCCGAAAGGAUGACAUGGAGCUGAGUGACUUACAUGGGAAGUGAUGCCACCAGGGCAGCCUCACCUCCUCCCCAUCAUCUUGUCCUAGAGUGGGCGUCACCUUGGAGCUUCUCUUCCUUCCGCCUCUGUUCCUCUUCUGGAGCCUUUGCCUCCCAUCUCUUAUCUCCUUGAUAUAAUUUUGAACUUGACCUACUUUAAACUUUUUUGCUCUGCAGCCUUCCUUGCCCUUCCACCUCCUCCUCCUAAUAUUCACUCUGGGCUCUUCUUCCCUUCCCACCCCUCACUCAGCUUCUCGUGGUGGCAGGAGGUAUGUCUGACAGGACAGAAGCAAGCUCCACUGUGGACAUGAGUGAUGGUGACAGCUGCUUUCAAAUUCUGCAUCUCAAGGCAGGGCAAGCCGGGGUGGUGCAGGUCUCAGGGCACGAGUCCCUCUCCCUUGGGUUCCAUUUUCUUGGAGCAGCCUAUUAGUUCUGGUGGGGUUGCCGUGUGUCGGAUGCAGCCCUGAGGGGCAGCUCGUGCCUGCAGCCCGGCAGCUCGUUCUCCUGUUCUGCUGUGCUGUGGGCUGGCACUCGAUACCUCUGGCAAGAGGAUGAUUAUCUACCUCACUGAUAAGAGGCAUCGCAUGGACGUUCUCUGGUCUGUAGUGGAGACAAGCAGUUAACCUAGCACCAUCCUCAUCCUCCCUGCAGAAGCCAUUAGCAGACCUUUGGGCCAGGGCAGCCUCCCUAUAAUUUUCUUCAUCUCUUGCUAAUCUCUAUAAUAAGGUUGCUUUUUCUUUCUUAGUUGAGUAAACAAGUAAGCCACAGUGUUUGAAAGGGAAAAACCAUAUUGCCUUGUGUGUUGCUUUUCCCAGUCAAAAGGGUCUGACCUUAGAAAGUCCCCACCAGUGAUGCUGAGUGUUCUGCUAUGGAAACAAUGCUGCUUUUCUCUCAGCUGUCCAAAGUUCAGCCGUUCCUCCUUCCCCUUCUCCCAGUGCGUUUGACUUUGUCAGGUCAGCCUCACUUGUCCCUUUCACAGUUGGCCCAUAAAGUCAUGUUUCUCUCCCUUUAGAAUAGGGAGGGGAAGGGAUCAGGUGUGUUGUCCUGGGCCUUUCAACCUUGCGGGCUGUGCUGAGUUCCAGAGAGCUGCCGGAAUUCCAGGUUUGACUCUCCAGCACAGAGCAGAGCUACACAGAGGUGACCCACGUUAGUCCACUGAGAGUUCUGAGUCCAAAGGGUGUACGUUGCAUAAGGCUAGAGACCGCUUUUCCUCCUUUCCCCCCAGGCUCUUUGUUUCCCUCCACCCACCCUUCCAUAUCCUCUGGAGCAGGAGACAAUGUGGGUGCCCAGAAGUGCCCUGCGCUUUCAGGCAGUGUCUCUGUUUUCCCAAGGUGAAACUUAGAUAUCAUGGACUGUUGUCCAGCCUCAAUGCUUCAUUUUCCCCUUGCAUAUCAACUGCCCUAAUCUGACUUUUUUUAAGUGCAAAUAAACUGCUAUAAGACAUUUUGGUUAGUAAAACUCUAGCCUUUGGCGUGUUGGUAUCUUGGAAGCAUUAGCUCUGAUAGGUCUAUAAGUGUAUUAAGGGACAUCCUUCCAUUUCAUUAGAGCAGCUUAAAAUGCUCAGGUGUCUGCCUUCUCUGGUGUUUCUUUGGGAUCUCUGUUUACCCACUUACGCUGGCUCCUUCUAGACAUUUCUUGCCACUUCCCCAACUAGACCACUCCUAGUGAUUACUGACUUUAGUGCCUAAACCUUUUUGGAAGGUUCUGGUUGGCUUGUUAGAGGAGCAUAUGAUUAGAAUUCUGUUUGGGGGUCUAGUUGUCUUGGAGCAAGUAUGUACUUAACUAGCCGAGAGAUGCUGCCUCUAGGCAGAGAGGAGGAGAGGUGUUGCCGGCUGGAGGGCCAACCAGUGAACACCAGCUGUGAAGGCCUUGGGAGAGGAGGAACAGGCCCUUGGGCAGAUGCAGGCAUUACCAGCAGGGAGCAGACUUACCUCCGAAGAUGGAGACAGGUGACUGAGAGCUGCAGGCCUCCUCUGCUCUUCCAAACACGUAGCAUUUGCACCCCUCCAAAGCCAUCUUUGUAAAGGAAAACGUAUUUGUAAUUGAAUCCAGAAGAAUUUAGUUACACAUAGACAUAACUCUUCAACCUUAACUAUGGCAAUACAUUUGUGCUUUAACUGUUACAUAGCAGUAUCACCACUUACCAGGAUCCAAAUCGAAAUAAUAAAAGCUGUCUCCAUAGUUUAAAAUCGAAUAGUGCCAUCAUCACAGUAUAUUAGUCAAAUAGAAGCUUCAUCAGAAAUGUAUCCCACAUAGAGUUUUAAGACUUGGAUUCUCUUCUGCCCUUGUUAAUCUCCAACUAAUUACUACAGAUUGACACGUUUUUAAUUAGCUGUCCUUUGUAAGAAGUCAGGAAAUCUGAUGCUGUGUCCAAAAUUAUGCACUGUUUGUUGAAGUAGAACCAGAAAUCCUGACCUCCUGUUAAAUGACAUCAGUUUCCCCCUCUGAGCAACAGACUGCUUGUCUUGCUAGGAGAGGAGGAUGGGGGGCUGAGCACUCAGGCUGUCCAUUGAAACCCCUUGUCCAUGAAUAGGGUCAUACUCCUAAGACUGAUGGGGUGUUGAUCUUCUAGGACAUCACUUGUUUAUUCAGUGCCCCAAACACAGAUUUCUCUUCUAGCACUUUAGAGUUGAUCCUUGAAGUCUCUCCUGGUUCAUUCAAAUACAAGCUGUGUGAGUCUGGUGGUUUUCUGUGAUUGGUCUAAUGUGAGCUCUUUGAACAGACAGAUCUGACAGUGAAUGACUCUCCCCUGCUUCUGGCAUAACUGCUUUGCCUCUGUCUAGUGUCCAAGCAUCUUAGCUGUUCAAGAGGAGAGGGCAGCAUAACUUCCUGACCACCGGUGUCAGAUAUCAGAGCAUUCUGGACUCCUGAGAGGCAGUGGCCUCUUGAGUGAACAGGGGAGGCCAGUAGAUGCCCCAGAUCCAGAGCCGUGGCUGCAAAUCCAGCAGGAAUAAGGAGGGACAACCACAGCCUCCUCAUCCAUGUGUCAUUUCCAAGGGUUUGCCUUGUGUCUCAGCUCAUUCUGGGCAGCACGUUUGUCUUCUGUCCCUAGAGAUUUGAAGGAUUUUGGACUCUUGUGAAUGGGUGACUGGACUUGGCUUUACAGAGUUGGGUGCUUUUUUCUCUCUGCAAUUACCUGUCAUAGCAUUUUGUGCUCACCACGAAGGAUGGUCUCUGCCUUCUCUUGUCGGUGUAUGCCAUCUGAACCUAGGAACACAAAGUAUAUUGGCCUCAAACGGAGACCCAGGGUUGCCAGUUUUCCGUGGGCCUUCCCCUCCCUUGAAAUGUCUUUAAUUACCUCCCCUUCAUCGUCAGGCCACGUGUGACUUCUGUUCUUAGCACUGCCAGGGUCAUUGACUUCCAUCUAAGCUUGCAUCAGGAAGAUGUUCCUUCUGUGAUCAUUGGUACUGAAGCCAGAAAAGCUCUCAUUCAGGAACUCUGAAGAGCAAAAAGGGACAAACACUAACUGCUGAGCUGGGCCAUUUGAUCUCCUUUCACCUUGCAUUGCUGUCACAGCACCUUGUAUGAUGGCAGGACAGGCUCCAGCAGAGAGAACUGCACAGUGACCACUGUAUUUUUCACGCUCUUCCAGGGAUCCCUGUCCCCCGACAUUGAAGAGAUCUCAUUCAGGCCAGAGACACAGAGACCACAUAGCCCAGUGAUUAAACCCCGGUUUCACUCUGGCCCCAGGAGUGGAGCCUGGCCACUCCUGUUUGGUUCUCACUGGGAGGCCCACUGGCCUUGGAUCAUCUCCUCAUGCACACCCGGAGUUUUACCUGCUUGCUUGCUUUCCUGGACUGCUGUUUGCAAGAAAGUAACUAAAACAUGAAAAGUAAACCUCCAGCUUCCACAGUAUAUUACCUGCCGUUGCAUGCAUUUGAAAGUUAGCCUCCUCCCUUGCCACCGUCUUGGUGGCAGUAGCGAUGCAAGAAUGAUGGGAGCUUUCCGAGAGCGUUCAGUGUUUCACUGAAGACAGGACCCAUAGCCUUCAUUUCUGGCUCUGUGUCUCCUCUGGCAUAUGGACACAUUUCCUGGCAUUUGCCUGAGUCUACACCACUUUUUGAGAACCUGAAAUAGAAGGGAAUCUUCUGUGGCCCACAGUCUCCAUAUUGGCACUAGAAGACUGGCCUGGCGGAGGAAUUUGCGUUGGCUUGCUUUCAGGGGUUAGCUACAAGAUUCAGCUUUAUAUCUCUGUUGCUUCUUGGCCAGUGUAGUCAAUAAGGGUCUUCUUUAACAUCUAAGAUAGAGGUUUGGUUGGCCGGGCGUGGUCGCUUACUCCUGUAAUCCCAGCACUUUGGGAGGCCCAGUGAGGUGGGAGAAUUGCUUGAACCCAGGAGGCAGAGGUUGCAGUGAGCUGAGAUUGCACCACUGCACUCCAGCCUGGGUAACAGAGUGAGACUCUUGUCUCAAAAAAAAAAAAAAAAAAAUCUAAGAUAGAGGUUUGGUCAACAGUGCUUAAUAAUAAAUAAGAACCUCCUGCCAUUCUAAUUUUCCUGCUGCACCCCAUCCCCCACACACCCCUCACGAACAUUGAUAUAAGCAGUAUUAACACAGUAUAAAGAAUGUUCACCUUGCAUAUGUCAUUUCAGGCACAUGGAUUCAGGAGAAGCACAGUUGAGUGGAAGAAAUGGUAGACUUGUGAGGCUUGCCCCAGGCCUUGUGUACACGCAAUAAGUGGUGAGCCAUGGGUCUCUCCGUCAGCGCCUCCCUCCCCGCCACCACUUCAGGCCAACAAUUUAAGGUGCUGAGUUGUAAGGCUCCUCCAUUGUCAGUACAGGGCUCGCCUUUGUAGCCCUGAUCACUACCAGUACACUUUUCAAGACAACUGAGUAUUUUUGUAUGCCUUUGCCUUCCCUUUGUCCAUGAAACAUGAAGAGUUGUUUAUGGUUCUUGACUUCUCUGAGCAGAGUGUCUGCAUCUCUUGGAGAGUUACACAUUUCUUCAUGAGCCAUUUUUCUCAUUCUUAGAUGCACCUGUUUUUAUCCUUUGCAGACCAUCUUCUGCCUUCUUAUUUUCCUGUCUGUCAAAGACAGAAAUUACAGGAGAUAGGGAGGGUUUUUUAGCAUCUCUUUCAAAAGAUGUAUGUCAGAAUUUCCUUUGCACACCAAGAACUGGAGCUUAGAGCCCCACUAUUCUCUAAGCCAGGUUCUAGUGCCUUACACUCCAGAAUGUCAGAUGGUGGGUGCAGAUUGGAAGAAAGAGAAAAGUUCAUCUCGGUGUGUGGGUUCCCAUCCGCCCCACAUAGCCUCUCCUUCUUCGGAACAAUGGGCGUGGGGUAGAAAGCUCUUUCAGUGAAGGGUGUUCUAGCAGCUCAGUUAACACUUUACUCUCCAGUCAACACUUGGGACAUAUAAAAAUGCCAUUGUAACUACUGUAGAGUCCUGUGACUCAUCGUUUGUGUUUGUCAAUUUGCAGUUCAGCUUAGCCCUUCCCUGUUCCUGUGUAGUUACAAUCUGGCCCUGAAGACAUCCGAGGCACUUCAGUAAGUGGGAUCUUUUCUAGAGAUCCUGGGUGACUUUGGGUGCACAGGGUGACCGAGCAUUUCUGCCCCUGUGAAUGUGGCACUAACACUGUGCACUGUCUCCACCAAGCAAGGUUUCCACUGAGUUUCUUCUCAUGUUACUGGGUUUGUAAAUGAAUAAACACAUUUUAACUACUCUUGCA